AGAGUUUCCCGGGCACUCACCGUGUGUAGUUGGCAUCUCCGCGCGUCCGGACACCCGAUCCCAGCAUCCCUGCCUGCAGGACUGUUCGUGUUCAGCUCGCGUCCUGCAGCUGUCCGAGGUGCUCCAGUUGGAGGCUGAGGUUCCCGGGCUCUGUAGCUGAGUGGGCGGCGGCACCGGCGGAGAUGCCUGGGAAGAAGGCGCGCAAGAACGCUCAACCGAGCCCCGCGCGGGCUCCAGCAGGACCGGCGGGUACGGCGGGUACGGCGAGGGACCAAGCCGGAUUUGCGAUUGGGAUGCAGCUGCGUUUCACCAGGGGCAAAAAGCUCCUUUCCUCCUCUCUUUCCUCCUCGCCACUUGCCCUUCCCCGGGGCCACGAGGAACAAGUGCAAGUGUAGGCGGCUGUCUCUAGGAGAAAGUCAUUGUCGCGGCAGAAGGGGCAGGAGAGAGCCCCGGGGACCGCCUGGACUCCCAGCGCUUCCAGAGACGGCCCCACAAGGGCCCCUGUGUUCAGGAGCCUAGAAAAUCUUGUAACAUUUAAAUAAUCGAUAUUGUGGGAGGUGGGGAUAGGAGAAUAGGAGUUAGUCCGCUCCUUUUUUUCAUUCAUUCAUUCGCACUCCCCACCCCGAUACAUACAGCUCCAUCGUAAGUUUUCAGGCCAGCGCCCCGGCCCCAUGCUUUUUCUAAAUCUAAACAGAGAACCCAGUCACUGCCCAGAGCCCGAAGUCUGUGUGGGCCAUACUGCUGUUGCAUCAGACGAUUAUACGCCCCCCCCACCUUUUAAGUUACUUUCAUUUUAUAGAGCUCCUGGGGCGUGCGAAGGAAGUGGUGCAUUGCAAAUGUGACCAUGCCUAAGUUGGUAACAGGCUGCUGUCUCUGGCGCUUGUGUGGGAUGGAAAAAGCUUUGUCUACCUUUUGUGAUGUCUUAGGAUUCUGACCUUGUUUCUUUCUGAAGGAUCUUACUUAUGCAUAGCACUUUCUGGUCCGACUUAAUUCCCAAGAACAGGAAGCAGCACAAAGUCCCUCUUAAACUUGAUUUGAUUGAUACUAAUACAUUUAUAGGUGUGUAAUGCAAUUUUUAAAAAAUUAAGGAAAUGACCGGGAAGUAUUUUCUGCCUUGUUUUCUACAUUUUUGGUGAAAGGGAUAACUUUUCCACUUAGAAUUCAGGGCUUCCAGUGUCGGACGCUGAAUGGUAUUUGGUUUUUCUUUUAGAACUGUAUAUUAAUAUAUCUCAAUCUCUGUAGACAACAUGUCUAUGUAAAUACUUCCCAACAUAUUUGAUCUUGUAGCCCAUAAAGAAUAACACCUUAAGGGAUUUAUUAGGUCUCUUGGUGUAGGAGUUAGGAAAGAUUUCACUCACUUCUUGUAGAGAGAAAUUGGUUGAAAUAUAGGUUUAAGAUUUUGCUUUACUAUAUAUUGACAGCUUUGAUUUAUUUUGAGCCUAAAUACGGUAUUUUCAGGGUCGAUUUAUAAAAUAGACCAGAUUUUAAUUUGUAAUCAUGAUUUUUUAAUGUUUGUAAUCAUGAAGUGUACCCGAAAGACCUCAAGCUGCUCUUUGAAAUAUUCAAGAAAAUUGAAAUUAUAGUCAGUAUAGAUACGAUAUUAUAGUCAGUAUAGUGUUAACUGCACUUACUGAAAAAAAGUGUACUUGGAAAUUAUAAGCAUCAUUUUUCUUAAUAUUCAGUUAGAAUAACUCAAUUCCAAAAAGUAGUAAACAUGUGAAUUAAACAUUGCUUAUUUUCUGCUCCUCUCAUUUCCAUAAAGGCAAUGGAUUGGUACAUAAUGGGGUUAUAGGAAGAAGUGGGUUUACAUUAAAAUAGAAAUGUUUAAAUUAUUUUAGAGAAUGUGGACUUAAUUUUAGAAUAAGAUUUUAUGAGUCUUUUAUGAAAAAAUAUCAGCGUUUUUUAACGAGAAAAAGAAUACCUCUAGAUUUGCCUAUAUAAUGAGAGUAUAACCUAAGCUGUAAAUUAUUGCCAUUUGAAAAUCAAAUCCUACUUGAAAGCCACACAGAACUUGACUUCUGUUUCCCAGCCAACCUUAAAUGAAGAGAAAAAGAUGACAUCAUCUAAGGCUGGUGACUUAUGCUACUCUUUGUAGCAUUGCUUUUAAAAUAAACAAAGUGGUUUUACAAUGUUCUCACAUCCCAAAGAAUGAUAAUGCUACUCUUUGUGGUAUUUGACAUAUUUGAAAGUAAGGUAACACUUGCCUCAUCCAGGAUGCGUUUUUUAAAAACUCAAAGUAAAUGUCUUUAUUCUUACCUUAACGAUUGCUUUCGGUGAGUCACAAUGUGUGUAAGUGUGUGUGUGUGUCACAUUUGGAAAACAGGUGCACAUAAAGCCAAAGUUAAGAGAAAUGCUUCCUGGGAUACUCAAUUUGUCACUAGUGUGGGCGUAUUAGGUUUUGCUGGUUACAGUCUGUAAUAUCAUCAAUGUUCAUGUCCAUGUUUUGCUUUCCUUCUCAGAGCUGGAAGUCGAGUGUGCUACUCAACUCAGGAGAUUUGGAGACAAACUGAACUUCCGGCAGAAACUUCUGAAUCUGAUAUCCAAACUCUUCUGCUCAGGAACCUGACUGCAUCAAAAACUUGCAUGAGGGGACUCCUUCAAAAGAGUUUUCUCAGGAGGUGCACGUUUCAUCAAUUUGAAGAAAGACUGCAUUGUAAUUGAGAGGAAUGUGAAGGUGCAUUCAUGGGUGCCCUUGGAAACGGAAGAUGGAAUACAUCAAAGUGAAUUUCUGUUCAAGUUUUCCCAGAUUAUCAUUCUUUGGGAUGAGAGAACAUUAUAAAACCACUUUGUUUAUUUUAAAGCAAGAAUGGAAGACCCUUGAAAAUAAAGAAGUAAUUAUUGACACAUUUCUUUUUUACUUAGAGAAUCGUUCUAGUGUUUUUGCCGAAGAUUACCGCUGGCCUACUGUGAAGGGAGAUGACCUGUGAUUAGACUGGGCGGCUGGGGAGAAACAGUUCAGUGCAUUGUUGUUGUUGCUGUUUUUGGUGUUUUGCUUUUCAGUGCCAACUCAGCACAUUGUAUAUGAUUCGGUUUAUACAUAUUACCUUGUUAUAAUGAAAAAACUCAUUCUGAGAACACUGAAAUGUUAUACUCAGUGUUGAUUUCUUCGGUCACUACACAACGUAAAAUCAUUUGUUUCUUUUGACUCAAAUUGUAUUGCUUCUGUUCAGAUGAUCUUUCAUUCAAUGUGUUCCUGUUGGGCGUUACUAGAAACUAUGGAAAACUGGAAAAUAACUUUGAAAAAAUUGGAUAAAGUAUAGGAGGGUUACUUGGGGCCAGUAAAUCAGUAGACUGAACAUUCAAUAUAAUAAAAGAACAUGGGGAUUUUGUAUAACCAGGGAUAAUAAAAAGAAAAAAGAAGUUAAUUUUUAAUUGAUGUUUUUGAAACUUAGUAGAACAAAUAUUCAGAAGUAACUUGAUAAGAUAUGAAUGUUUCUAAAGAAGUUUCUAAAGGUUCGGAAAAUGCUCCUUGUCACAUUAGUGUGCAUCCUACAAAAAGUGAUCUCUUAAUGUAAAUUAAGAAUAUUUUCAUAAUUGGAAUAUACUUUUCUUAAAAAAAAGGAACAGUUAGUUCUCAUCUAGAAUGAAAGUUCCAUAUAUGCAUUGGUGAAUAUAUAUGUAUACACAUACUUACAUACUUAUAUGGGUAUCUGUAUAGAUAAUUUGUAUUAGAGUAUUAUAUAGCUUCUUAGUAGGGUCUCAAGUAAGUUUCAUUUUUUUUAUCUGGGCUAUAUACAGUCCUCAAAUAAAUAAUGUCUUGAUUUUAUUUCAGCAGGAAUAAUUUUAUUUAUUUUGCCUAUUUAUAAUUAAAGUAUUUUUCUUUAGUUUGAAAAUGUGUAUUAAAGUUACAUUUUUGAGUUACAAGAGUCUUAUAACUACUUGAAUUUUUAGUUAAAAUGUCUUAAUGUAGGUUGUAGUCACUUUAGAUGGAAAAUUACCUCACAUCUGUUUUCUUCAGUAUUACUUAAGAUUGUUUAUUUAGUGGUAGAGAGUUUUUUUUUUCAGCCUAGAGGCAGCUAUUUUACCAUCUGGUAUUUAUGGUCUAAUUUGUAUUUAAACAUAUGCACACAUAUAAAAGUUGAUACUGUGGCAGUAAACUAUUAAAAGUUUUCACUGUU